GAUUGCAGGUGAUCCACCCACCUCUGCCUCCCAAAGUGCUGGGAUUACAGGCGUGAACUACCAUGCCUGGCCUGUUUUCAUUCGUAUCAAGCUUAAAGAAAUAGUAAAAGGCUUUAAAUAAAAUAGACAAUAAGCCUCCUGGUCUACCCGCUGCUCCUGGUCUACCUGCUAUCUGCUGUGCACCUUCCCUCUUCCAUCCUGUGUCCCCAGAAGCAGCCACUUUGGGCUCCGUUUCGUCUUCUGCUGUCGACCUCCAGCUUCUAAUAUGGUCACAUCGAAGUGACUUGUUUCAUGUUUCUUCUCCCUCAGAUUUAAAGUAACCAGCUUGAUAAGCACCUCAACGUAAUAAGGGCACAGUAGUGGCUUCAUUUUUCUCAUCACAGCCUCAGGCUUCCUGUCAGCCCUUCCCUAGUGCUCGUCGUGAGGAGAGCUGAUGAUGCUCUGGUCACAGCCUUGUUUGUUAUUGACUCUCAGUUACUUUCAGGUAUGGGAAAGUUCAGUCCACACUCUCACUCCAAGCUCUUGUACCUCCCCUCAUUCUAGCCUGCAGAGGGGAGAUGGAGGAGGCUUGUCUGUAUUCCCACUUCAUUUACUUGUUGCCCUCCGACGGGGGCUCCUUCUGGGUUGGGGUGGGAAAAUCAGUGGUUAGAGAAAAAGACACAGAGUCUCCUGUUGUGCGGUGGUCAGUACCCAGAGUUAUGACAGGCAUCAGUGGGGCUUGGUUGGAGCCUCUGACAGGGCUCUGCCCUGCAGUUCCAUGGUGUAUGUGAUUCUUUCUCUCACUGCAUGCAGACUCACCCAGAAGUCCACUCACUGCCUCUUCCCCUGGGGUCUCCCUCCCUGCAGGUAGUGCUGCUGAGGAGGAGCCUGCUAAUGAGCUCAAGUGUCAAGUUCGGGAAUCUUCUGGGUGUUCCUUGGGCCCAGGGAAACAGUGCCCUGCCUGAGGGAUUAUUGUCAUUCAAGGAUAUAUCUAUGGAGUUCACCUGGGAUGAAUGGCAGCUACUGGAUUCUACACAGAAGUACCUGUACAGAGAUGUGAUAUUGGAAAACUAUCAUAACCUGAUAUCAGUGGGGUAUCAUGGUACCAAGCCUGACUUAAUCUUCAAGUUGGAACAAGGAGAAGAUCCAUGGAUAAUAAAUGCCAAAAUUUCCAGGCAGAGCUGUCCAGAUGGCUGGGAAGAAUGGUACCAGAACAAUCAAGAUGAGCUUGAGAGUAUUGAAAGAAGCUAUGCUUGUAGUGUGUUGGGAAGACUUAAUCUGAGCAAAACCCAUGAUUCUUCAAGACAGAGACUCUAUAACACACGUGGAAAAAGUUUGACACAAAACUCAGCUCCAAGCAGAAGUUAUUUAAGAAAGAAUCCUGAUAAGUUUCAUGGUUAUGAAGAACCAUAUUUUCUUAAGCAUCAAAGAGCUCAUAGCAUAGAAAAAAACUGUGUGUGUAGUGAAUGUGGGAAAGCUUUUCGUUGUAAGUCACAGCUCAUUGUACAUCUCAGAAUUCAUACAGGAGAGAGACCUUAUGAAUGCAGUAAAUGUGAAAGAGCCUUCAGUGCCAAGUCAAACCUUAAUGCUCAUCAGAGAGUUCAUACAGGAGAAAAACCCUACUCAUGUAGUGAGUGCGAGAAGGUCUUCUCUUUCAGGUCACAGCUCAUUGUCCAUCAGGAAAUUCACACAGGAGGGAAACCCUAUGGCUGCAGUGAAUGUGGGAAAGCCUACAGUUGGAAAUCACAGCUUCUUUUACACCAGAGAAGUCACACAGGAGUGAAACCGUAUGAAUGCAGCGAAUGUGGGAAAGCCUUUAGUUUGAAGUCUCCAUUCGUUGUACACCAGAGAACUCAUACAGGAGUGAAACCCCAUAAAUGCAGUGAAUGUGGGAAAGCCUUUAGGAGUAAGUCCUAUCUCCUUGUUCACAUCCGAAUGCAUACAGGAGAAAAACCCUAUCAAUGCAGUGAUUGUGGGAAAGCCUUCAAUAUGAAGACACAACUCAUUGUACAUCAGGGAGUUCACACAGGAAAUAAUCCUUAUCAAUGCGGUGAAUGUGGGAAAGCCUUUGGUAGGAAGGAACAGCUCACUGCACAUCUGAGAGCUCAUGCAGGAGAGAAGCCCUAUGGAUGCAGUGAAUGUGGGAAGGCUUUCAGCAGCAAGUCAUACCUUGUUAUACAUAGGAGAACACACACCGGAGAGAGACCCUAUGAAUGUAGUUUGUGUGAGAGAGCCUUUUGUGGAAAAUCACAGCUGAUUAUACAUCAGAGAACUCAUUCAACUGAGAAGCCCUAUGAAUGCAAUGAAUGUGAAAAAGCCUACCCUAGGAAGGCAUCACUUCAGAUACACCAGAAAACUCAUUCGGGAGAGAAACCUUUUAAAUGCAGUGAAUGUGGAAAAGCCUUCACUCAGAAGUCAUCUCUCAGUGAACAUCAGAGAGUUCACACCGGAGAGAAACCAUGGAAAUGCUCUGAAUGUGGGAAAUCCUUCUGUUGGAAUUCAGGGCUUCGUAUACAUCGGAAGACUCAUAAAUGAGAAAUCAGAAUGAUGCAAUGUGAGAAACUGAUGUUCAGGAGACUUCGGAUAAUAUAGACAGGAUUUACAAGCAGGAGGCCCUAAAAUUACACUCAUGUCAAAAAUCAGAGAGGAGAGAGACCAACCAUAUUUGGGAUGAGUGUAAAAGCUUUCAGAAAUAAGUUACAAAUCUUUGUAGAUGAAAAUAAUGGAAGGAAUGUGGAGCAAUAAAUGUAUCAAAUGUUGUAGUAUCAUCAUGAAGAUUCAGAGAAUUUACACUAGGAACACCUUAUAAGUUGAAUAAAUUAAGGAAGCAUUUUCCCAUUGAAAGUGUGUUCCAUGGAAAGUCACAUUCCAGAUUUGAAGCUGUGUUUUUGUAAAAUAAAAUCUUGGUAUGAACAGUUGACUUCAUGGUGGAGUAUAAAGUUGUUUUUUUAAAAAUAUGUAAAUAAUGUUCAGGAAAAACGCAGGGAACAGAGUCUUAAAGUUAAUGGAUAUUUAAUGUGACUUUCCUGAGUUAACACUGAAUAGUAUUUCUAAAAUUUUUUGUACUUUAUUUUUUAAUGUAACUUGUUCUAUCUAUCUAUAUAUAUAUUUGAUAGUUUGUGGAAUAAUAUCCCCCAGUAUUUUCCAUAUUAAAUGCUAAUUAUCUUUUGAUUUCUUUUUCAUAAGCAGAUCUGGCAUUUAUUACAGGGCUGCCGCUUAAGAGAACUCAUUAUAAUGAACGUUUAUUAUAUUUUGCAGUUCCAUGCCUGUUGUCCAUUGAUUGACAUGAGCACCCCUGUUUUCUCUGGAGAAAUACCUCCCCUCUCUGGGGUGCUUCCUGUGGUAGUGUCUUUCAGGUAUCCGUUCCACUAGCUACAGGUGAGCAUUUUACCCAUUGUUGGAUAAUGGUAAUCUCUUUUUCAGAAUUUUGAGUCUGUAAUUCAUUUGUACAUGAACCAGAAAAUGUGGGAACUCAUUCAUUCUUGUCCCAGAAUUCUGUUGAGAACAUCCAUUCAUUCUGGCUAAUUGAUUACAAGAAUAACUGUGGAUACGAUCCCUUUAGAACCUGCUUCUCUGAUCUGUGUGUUUCCUCACUUCUCAAUAAAAAUGUCUUUUGCUUUUUGUUGUUUGGGUUUUUUUUUUUUUUUUUUUUUUUUUUUUUUUGAGACUAAGUUUCACUCUUGUCCUCCAGGCUGGAAUGCAAUGGCAUGAUCUCAGCUCACUGCAACUUCCACCUCCUGGGUUCAAGCAAUUUCCUUGCCUCAGCCUCCCAAGUGGCUAGGAUUACAUGCCUGGCUAAUAUUUGUAUUUUUAGUAUAGACGGGGUUUCACCAUGUUGGCCAGGCUGGUCUUGAACUCCUGACCUCAGGUGAUCUGCCCACUUCAGCCUCCCAAAGUCAUGGGAUUACAGGUGUGAGCCACCGAGCCCGGCCAGCUUUCUAUUUCUUAUAACCUAAGGGCUUUAACUGAUCAGUUGUUGCCUUGGUAGCAUGUAGUUAACAAAGUGGGGUAUAUGAUUUAGGUUUGUUUGUUUUUCCUGAGACAAGAAAAUCACAUUCUUGUUUAUAUUUGAAGAUAGCAACUUUUAGCCAUCAUGUGAAAUAUGGUUAUUGUUUCUGUACACCUGGAACGUUGUAGUGCCUGAUACUGAAAUUUUGGAAACACUGAAGAAUUAUAGCAUUAUAAGAAUUUUAAAUUUAUGAGAAAAUCUGAGACAGGGGCAGAGAUGGCUGAUUUUGAUCUUGCUGGAUCUUAGACCAUGAGAAUGACAGGCCUGAAGCCCUGAAAUCUCACCUCAGGGUGGAGUGUCAGACUUGGCAACUUUGACAUUGCUGAAAAAGUUUCUUACAGCUGUAGGAGUGAGGUGGUGGGAAUCAAAUAGUAUAUUUGGCUUGGUGAAUUAAAGUCAGUUCACCUCAAAUGUUUACUAAAUCCCUUAAUGUAAACAUGUGUUGAAAAAGUUAUCCUCACCCUUCCCCCCCUCAAAAAGUUAUCCCUUGAUAAUUUGAAUAGGAAUAUCUGGGAAGAACCUGAGGACUCAGCCUAGCAAGCUCUUGUGAUAGACUUUGAAUAGCAGUAUCUGCGAAGAACCUGAGGCCUCAGCCUAGCAAACUCUUCUGAUAGACUUUGAAUAGGAAUGUCUGGGAAGAACCUGAGGACUCAGCCUAGCAAACUCUUCUGAUAGACUUUGAAUAGGAGUAUCUGGGAAGAACCUGAGGACUCAGCCUAGCAAACUCUUCUGAUAGACUUUGAAUAGGAAUGUCUGGGAAGAACCUGAGGACUCAGCCUAGCAAACUCUUCUGAUAGACUUUGAAUAGGAGUAUCUGGGAAGAACCUGAGGACUCAGCCUAGCAAACUCUUCUGAUAGACUUUGCACUGCAGAUGCUUCAUUUAAGGCUAUAGAGUAGAUGUUGGCAAUAUAUAAAAUUCAAACUUGAGUGUCCAUAAAUAACUGUUGUUGGAACAUGGCUAAAUAUAUUUGUGUAUUAUUUGACUGCUUUUGCACAGCCAUGGCACAGUUGAGUAGUUGAGGUAUAAAAAACCUGCCACCUCCUGAUACAGAUAGAACCCCUUCCCUUUUCUGGGAAAAUGUGGAAUUUGCCUUGCAGGAGGAAGCUUAUUCUGCCAGUUCCCCAUGGCUUAUUUUUACCAGUUUGGUAACAAUAAUCUACACUAAACAUGCCCUGGGAUGGGAUUGCUCAUUUAGGAAAAUAUGUAGAAUUCAUAGAGCAUUGCAGGAAUGAGUAAUGUAUCAAAACUUCUCAGCAUGACAACACCCAGGGCAACGUGACAAAACCCUGUCUACAAAAGUUUCUUAAAAGCUGGUUACAGCGGUGCACACCUGCAAUCCCAGCUACUCAGGAGGUUGAGGCAGGAGGAUCACUUGAGCCCAGGAGGUCAAGGAUGCAGUGAGCUGCACUGUACUCCAGUCUGGGCAACAGUGAGACCCUGUCUCAAAAAAAAAGUUGGGGGAGGGGGUAGAUACUUGUGAAAUCCUUUGAGGGUGUUCAGUGAAGGGCAAUUACUUACAGCAUAUACUUGGUGCACUGACACCCAGCAGUGAUGAUGGUUUUGCUUUCUGUUUUUUUUUUUGUUUUGUUUUGUUUUUUUUUUUUUUUGAGACGGAGUCUUGUUCUGUCACCCAGGCUGGAGUGAAUUGCACAAUCUCGGCUCACUGCAACCUCCGCCUCCUGGGUUCAAGCGAUUCUCCUGCCUCAGCCUCCAUAGUAGCUGGGAUUACAGGUGUGUGCCACCGCGCCUGGCUAAUUUUUGUAUUUUUAGUAGAGACGGGGUUUCACCACGUUGGCCAGGCUGGUCUUGAAUUCCUGACCUCAGGUAAUCCACCUGCCUCGGCCUCCCGAAGUGCCGGGAUUACAGGCGUGAGCCACCAUGCCUGACCAUGAUGAUGGUUUUAAAAGUUAGCUGUAGCAGCUAAGGCAAGACCAGAUCCAACACUGGCUUAUGGCAAGGGGAAGAACAAAAGUCAGGAACUUUGCCAUAAUCUAGAAGAAAGAAUGAUAAUGCUUUGUGACAUGCUGGAUUGUAUCCAUUAUGUGUUCCUAAGACCCUCAGCCCUCUCCCUCCACCAAGACCCAAUAAAAGUGUGUUAUUGAAAGUAGUAGCUACUGGCCGGGCGUGGUGGCUCACGCCUGUAAUCCCAGCACUUUGGGAGGCCAAGGUGGGUGGAUCACAAGGUCGGGAGUUCGAGUUCAGCCUGGCCAAUAUGGUGAAAUCCCGUCUCAACUAAAAAUACAAAAAUUAGUCGGGCAUGGUGGCGGGCGCCUGUAAUCCCAGCUACUUGGGAGGCUGAGGCAGGAGAAUCGCUGGAACCCGGGAGGUGGAGGUGGCAGUGAGCAGAGAUUGCGCCAUUGCACUCCAGCCUGGGUGACAGAGUGAGACUCUGUCUCAAAAAAAAAAAAAAAAAGAAAAGAAAAUGACAAACACAUGUUCUGUGUAUAUGACACAAUCCUAACUGUGGCAUGUAUCUAUGUCUUCACUUGCAUCGGCCUCAAUUAUCAACUUGUGGCAAAAGAAUAAGAAAGAGAACUAAAAAAUGAAAAAAAAUAAGAUGCUUUCCUAUGGUCCCAGCUACUUGGGAGGCUGAGGCAGGAGUGUCGCUUCAGCCCAGAAGGUUGAGGAUGCAGUGAGCCAUGAUUGUGUUUCAGCCUGGAUGACAGGGCAAGACCUCAUAUCUGUAAAAAGUAAAAAUAAAUAAACAAACUAUAUAAUAAUAAUACAGAAGACAAAUGUCAAUGUUGCUGAAAAGCCAAAAGAAGCCAAGAGGACAGUCUUCUGAGUAGAGGGCAUAGGAGUUCCCAAAGAGGAAAGUCCAGUCUGAGAUCAGGCUGGAGGCCAAAAGGAACUCUUGACCUGAGACAGUUGGAAAUAUUACUUCUACUGGCAAAUAAAAGUGCUUCAAGCAGACGUUUAUUUAGAAAUUCAUGCUGCAUGUUUAUUGAUGGAAUGUUUGUGUGACUCUUUAAUAGAAGUCUGAACUAGGUAUGCCAUAUAUUUCCAUAUAUCUUCAUUUGUCUUGGGGGUAAGUGUUGAGAGAAGGAAGUGGCUUUUGGUUUUGUGAGUGUCUUGAAGAUCUAAGGUUUAUUGUGAAAAAGUGUAGGGGUAAUUUUUUUUUUUUUUUUUUUUUGAGACAGAGUCUCACUGUGUCACCCAUGCUGGAGUGCAGUGGCGUGAUCUCGGCUCACUGCAACUUCCGCCUCUGGGGUUCAGGUGAUUCUCCUGCCUCAGCCUCCUGAGUAGCUGGGAUUACAGGCACCUGCCACCACACCUGGCUAAUUUUUGUAUUUUUAGUAGAGAUGGGGUUUCACCAUUUUGGCCAGGAUGGUCUCAAACUCCUGACCUCAGGUGAUCCACCCGCCUUGGCCUCCCAAAGUGCUAGGAUUACAGGCAUGAGCCAUCGUACCCGGCCAGAGCAUCCUUAAUUUUUAAAAACAAUUUAGCUACUUUUUUUUUUUUUUUUUAACUAUUUUAAGAGCAUCACAGUAAAAGGAAAAUAACAGCUCACUUUGGGGCCAAAGUCUAAAAUUUAAAAUCAGCCCUACUCUGGCUGGGUGCAGUGGCUUAUGCCUAUAAUCCCAACACUUUGGGAGGCAGGAGGAUCACUUGAGCUCAGGAAUUUGAGACCAGUCUGGACAACAAAGCAAAACCCCAUCUCUGAAAAAAAAAAAAUACCCCGGGAUGGUGGCUUAGGGCUGUGGUCCCAGCUACUCUGGAGGCUGAGGCAGGAGGAUUGCUUGAGCCCAGGAGGUUGAAGCUGCAGUAAGCCAUAUUUGUACCACUGCACUCCAGCCUGGGUGACAGAGCAAGACCUUGACUCAAAAAAAAAAAAAAAUUCUACUCUCUUGGUAUUUGUAAUAUGUUAUGAGAUACCAUCAUUGGAGGUUGUAAGGAUGGGAAUAUUAGUUGAAAGUCUGAUAUUUUAUCAUUGAGUUGCCCUUUUCCAAUUUUACAUGCUUAGGUUGACUUCUCAAUAGCAACAGUAAAAAUCAGAAGACAGUAAAAGAAUGUCUUCAAUGUUCUGAAAGAAAAUAUCUACCUAGAAGGGUUAUUCACAAACCAGGGUGAAAUAAUGUCAUUUUAAACAAAAUAUUUAAUACCAAGAAAGUUGGAAACAUAAAAAAAUAAAAAGUCAUGCUCGGCCAAAUCUAAACAGACUUAAAAAUUAUAAGAUGUAAUUUGAUGGUACAAAAAUAUGGAAAUAAGCCCCAGAAAAUAACAGUAUGUAACAUUGGAAGAAGUCUAAUAAUUUUUAGGGGAGUAGAGAUUCUGAUUAUCCCACAUGGCAGGGCAUUAGACAAGGAGACCCACUUUACCACAGAUAAGGUUCAGUGGUGGUCCCAUGACUGAUCUAUUGGUCACACCUUAUGCUUACCCCACCACCUAGAAGCGGCUGGUGUGACAGAGCAUUGGAUGACCUGCUGAAGGUGGUUUGAAGUACCAGCUUAGUGGCAGUACUUGACAAGCACAGGGCACCGUCCUCCAAGAUGCAGUCCUGGAAUCACAGACUUUUAUCUGGUAGUGAUUCCUCAAUAGGGAGUGUACACAGGUCCAAGAGCCAAGGAGUGGGAACGGGAUCAGCUCCACUUAACAUCAUUUCCAGUGAUCAGUUUGGAGACUGAAGAGCAACAGUCUGAGGAAUGACCCCAGGCAGUAAUUUGUUUCCACAGAAAAAACAAAGAGCACCAGUAAAGGGUAAUUAUGUAAUAAUAAAAGAUAGUGCAAGUGCAGAUUUCUUAUUUUAUUAGUAACUGAUUAAUAAUUAUAGGCCAGGCGUGGUGGCUCACGCCUGUAAUCCCAGCACUUUGGGAGGCCGAGGUGGGCGGAUCACAAGGUCUGGAGGUCAAGACCAUCCUCACUAACAUGGUGAAACCCCAUCUCUAUUAAAAACACAAAAAAUUAGCGGGGCGUGGUGGCGGGCGCCUGUAGUCCCAGCUACUCGGGAGGCUGAGGCAGGAGAAUGGCUUGAACCCAGGAGGCAGAGGUUGCAGUGAGCCGAGAUCACGCCACCGCACUUCAGCCUGGGCAACAGAGUGAGACUCCGUCUCAAUAACAGCAACAAAAAAAGCAAUUAUAUAAAACAAUAUGCAGUACUGUUUGGACUAUAACAUACAGAAGUGUAAUAUGUCUACCAAUAACACCACAAAGGAGGAGGAUGGGAGAAGAGUCGUGUUGGGGUAAGGAAAUGGCUCUAGAUGGCAACUUAAAGCCACAAGAAUAAGCUGAGAGAACCAGAAAUAGGAAAUAAAUAGGCUACUGUAACAAAAGCUGUUAAUAUAUACUUUCUCUUCAUCUCUCAGCCUCUUUAAAUUAUAAAAUAUAUAAAGCAAUAUUUAUAGCAAUGUGUUGUUGCAUUUGUAACAUAGAUAUAUAUAUCAAUACCAGCACAAAAGUCGGGGUGGGGGCUAGAACUAUAUAGGAAUAAUGGGUUUAUAAAAGUCUUAUUGGAAUUAAGGUAGUAUAAAUCUGAAGUAGACUCUGAUAAGUUAAUGUGUAUUUAACACUUCCUAGAACAAACACUAAAGAAAUAACUGCAAAAAUAUUGUAAGGAAUCAUUAAAUAAAUAAAAUAUUACAUUACAAAAUAUGCACUUAAGACAAAAGUGAAGGAGAAAUAGAUGAACAAAAGAUACAUGAGACAUAAAAUACAAAAGGGAAAGCAGCAUAUGUAAAUCUAACUAUAUCAAUAAUAACUUUUUUUUAAGAGGGUCUUGCUCUAUUGCCCAGGCUGGAGUGCAGUUGCAUGAUCAUAGCUCACUGCAGCCUUGAACUCUUGGCUUCAAGCAAUUCUCCCACCUCCCACCUGGCUAUUUUAUUUUAUUUUAUUUAUUUAUUUAUAGAGAUGGAGGUAUCAAACUCCAGGGCUCAAGCAAUCCUCCCAUUCUGGUCUCUCGAAGCAUCAAGAUUAUAGGCAUGAGCCAGCGCACCUGGCCAGUAAUAACAUUAAAUGUGAAUAGAUUAAACUAUCAAAAGACACAGAUUGUCAAAGUGGUGAUAAAAAAAAAUCCAACCAUGUACAGAAGACAUACAUACAUACUCAAAGAUACAAUUGGAUUAGAAGUAAAGGAUGGAAAAAGAUAUAAAACGCAAACAGCAACCAUAAUAAAUCUCCAGUGGCUUUCUAAUAUCAGACACAAUAGAGUUUAAAACAAAAGUUUUACUAGAGAUAAAGAAAAGUAUUUUGUAAAGAUAAGUCAUCAAGAAGAUGUAACAAUUAUAAAUAGACAAUUGGGAUUACAUCAAGCUGGGAAGCUUCCAUACUGCCGAGGAAAUAACAAAAUAAAGAGACAACCCACAGAUUGGGAGAAAAUAUUUGCAAACUAUCCAUUUGACAAGGGGUUAAUUGCCAGAAUAUACAGGGAGCUCAAACAACUCUAUAGCAAAAACAAAGAAAAAUAACAAAAAAAAAACCCCAAACUCCAGAUAUUCCAAUUAUAAAGUAGGCAAAAGAUCCAAACAGACGUUUCUCAGAGAAGACAUGCAAAUGUCUAACAGGUAUAUGAAAAAAUGCUCAAUAUCACCACUUAUCAGAGAAAUGCAAAUUAACCACAAUCAGAUAUCAUCCCUCUUCAGUUAAAAUGGCUUGUAUCAGAAAGACAGGAAAGAACAGAUGCUGGUGAGGAUAUGGAGGAAGGACAGCCCUCGUACACUGUUGGUGGGAGUGGAAAUUAGUACAGCCACUAUGGAGAACAGUAUGGAGGCUCCUCAAAGCAACUGAAAAUAGAACUAUUAUACGAUCCAGCAACCCCACUACUGGGUGAAAAGCCAAAAGAAAGGAAAUCAGUACAUCAAAGAGACACCUGCACUCUCACGUUUCCUGCAGCACUAUCCACAAGAGCCAAAAAAUGAAAUCAGGCCAGGCGUGGUGGCUCACGCCUGUAAUCCCAGCACUUUGGGAGGCUGAGGUGGGUGGAUCACUUGAGGUCAAGAGUUCAAGACCAGCUUCACCAGCCUGGUGAAACCCCGUCUCUACUAAAAAUACAAAAGUUAGCGGGGUGUGGUGGCAGACACCUGUAGUCCCAGCUACUCGGGAGGCUGAGGCAGGAGAAUCACUUGAACCCGGGAGGCGGAGGUUGCAGUGAGUUGAGAUUGAACUGCUGCCCUCCAGCCUGGGCGACAGAGUAAAGCUCCAUCUCAAAAAACAAAACAAAAAAAAAAUCAGAGCCCAUCAACAAAUGGAUAAAGAAAGUGUGAUAUAUAUAAACACAGUCAAUAUGUCUAUUCAGUCAUAAAAAUAAAAUCCUGUCAUUUGCAGCAACUGGGAUGGAACUGAAAGCCAUUAUAAUAAGUGAAAUAAGCCAAGCACAGAAAGACAAAUAUUGCAUGUUCUCACUCAUAUUUGAAAGCUAAAAAAGUAGACCUCAUGAAGAUAGAGUUGAUGGUGGUUACCAGAAGCUGGGAAGAGGGGGAAGGAUGAAGGGGAAAAAUAUGAAUGUAUCUAUUAUUGCUGAACUGUACACUUAAAAAUGGUAAUGAUGAUAAUAUUUAUAAUAUAUUUACAUUUUGUUUAUAUAUUUAUAUUUUGCCUCAAAAAAGGCAAAAAAGAAGAUAUAAUAAUUAUAAACAUGUAUGUACCUAAUAACAGCACCAAAAUACAUGAAGCAAAAUCUGACAGAAAUGAAGAGAGACAACUCAACAAUACUAGUUGGAGACUUAAUAUCCCACUUUCAAUAUUAGAACAAUCGUAUAAGUUGUCUAGGACUGUCGUAACAAAGAACCACAAACUGGAUGGCUUAAACAACACAGAUAUAUUGUCUUACUGUUCUGGAGCCUCCAUGUUUGAAAUCAAGGCAUUGACAGGUUUUGGUUCCUUCUGAGGGCUCUGAGGGAAGGAUCUGUUCCAGGCCUCUCUCCUUGGCUUGUAGAUGGCUGUCUUCUCACUGUCUCAUCACAUAAUCUCCCUUCUAUAUGCACAUAUCUCUGUGCAAACGUCCCCUUUUUAUAGGGACAUCAGUCAUAUUGACUCCUAAGUCCUCAUUUUAACAUUGUUAACUCUGUACAGACCCUCUCUCCAAAUAAGGCCUCACUCUGAGGUAUGGAAAUUAGGACCCCAACAUAUCUCUUUGAGUUGGGGGGACACUACUCAACACUGAAGUGUUUAGGGAUGUCGAGAAAUUAUGCCUCCAACCUAUGCUCAUACAUUUUUUUUUUCUUUUUCAUUUUUUUUUUUUUUUUUUGAGACGGAAUCUCACUCUGUCACCAAGGUUGAAGUGCAGUGGCACCGUGUCGGCUCACUGCAACCUCUGCCUCCCGGGUUCAAGUGAUUCUCCAGCCUCAGCCUCCUGGGUUCAAGUGAUUCUCCAGCCUCAGCCUCCUGAGUAGCUGGGAUUACAGGUGCCCACCACCACGCCCAGCUAGUUUUUAUAUUUUUAGUAGAGACAGGUUUUCACCAUGUUGGCCAGGCUGGUCUUGAACUCCUGACCUCAGGUGAUCCACCCACCUCGGCCUCCCAAAGUGCUGGGAUUACAGGCGUGAGCCACUGUGCCCUGCCAAUGCUUAUACAUUUCAAGAAAAACAUUUAUUUGGCCGGGCAUGGUGGCUCACAUCUGUAAUCCUAGCAUUUUGGGAGGCCGAGGCGGGUGGAUCACCUGAGGUUGGGCGUUUGAGAACAACCUGGCCAACAUGGUGAAACCCCCGUCUCUACUAAAAAUACAAAAAUUACCCAGGCGUGGUGGCAGGCACCUGUAAUCCCAGCUACUUGGGAGGCUGAGGCAGGAGAAUUGCUUGAACCCGGGAGGCAGAGGUUGCAGUGAGCCGGGAUCACACCACUGCACUCCAGCCUGGGUGACAGAGUGAAACUGUCUCAGAAAAAAGAAAGAAAGAAAAACGUUUAUUUGUAGAGAAAGCUAACAUGGUAAAAAUUUGAGGAAUAUUGGUAAAGAAUAUUUACAAAUUCAUUAUCAUUGUGUAAAUUCUAUAUUACUUUUUAAACUUUCAUGUUUUGUGGAGUCAUUUCUAAAUCAAAUCAUUAAAAAGAGGCCAGGUGUGGUGACUCACGCCUGUAAUCCCAGCACUUUGGAAGGCCAAGGUGGGCGGAUCACUUGAGGUCAGGAGUUUGAGACCAGUCUAGCCAACAUGGUGAUAGCCCCUGUUUACCAAAAAUACAAAAAUUAGCCAGGGUGGUGACGUGCACCUGUAAUUCCAGCUACUCGGGAGGCUGAGACGGGAGUAUCACUUGAACUCGAAAGGUGGAGGUUGCAGUGAGCCGGGAUCACAUCACUGCACUCCAGCCUGGGUGACAGAGUGAGACCCUGUCACACACAAAAAAUUAAAGUCAUUAAAAAGAAAAACUGAAUUUUGCAAAAUUAUUGGAUGUCAGUAUAUUCAAAUCAAUUUUAUUUCUAUAUAUCAGAAAAAUAAUAUAAAAUGGGAUUUAACAAAUUGAAUCAAUUUUCAGUGGCAUCAAAAUACAAAAUAGAUACAAAUCUUAUGGUGUUGGAACUGUUCAGCAUCUUGAAGGUGGUUGUUGAUACAUGAACCUACACUGGUGAUAACAUUGAACAGAACUUAAUAUACACACAUACAAAGUAUAAGUAAAACUGGGGAAAUGUUAAGUAUUGUGUGUCAGUAUUCUGGCUGUGAUAUACUGUAGUGUUGCAAAAUGUUAGCAUUGGGGGAAACUGGGAAAAGUGUAUAAGGGAUCUCUGCAUUAUUUUGUAUACUCUAGGUGAAACUAUCUCAAUACAAAUUUAAUUAAAACAAAAUAAAUCUGAUAAAGAUGUAAAAGAAUAAAGAGACUAUUAUCCAGUUGAUAAAAUAUGCAACUAUGAAAUAAACUGAAUAAAUUGAACAAGCUUGAACAAAUUGAAUCAUCAAUAUGUUCAAGUCCUAGACAUUUAAUAGUGAUAAAUGUUAUUCCCCAAAUACUGUAUGUAGUAUAACAUCUUUGUUAAAGGCCAAGAUAAAGCAAAAUGGAGUUAUAUAUUGUUUAGGCAUAUGUGUUUAUGUGACAAAACAACGGGGAAAAAAAGCUAGAAAAUGAUAAUCAAAAUCUUUAGGAUAGUGUCUACACCCUGUGGAAGAAGCAGUGAGUUGGAAAAAGGGAACACUAAGUAGAGGCUUCAAGUUAUUUUUAAUUUUCUGUUUGGGUGAAAGAUUCAAGAGCAUUCGUGAGAAUGUACUUGUAACUAGUAUUUGAUGAACAGGGGCUAUACAACAGUUUAGAUUUUAAAAAAUUAUGGGAGAAUACUAAGGAUAACCAUACGCCAGUCAAAUAAAAAUAGAUAACACAUUUUUCAGUUUUCUAGAAUACUGCACAUUAUCAAAACUGACCAAAGCAGAAAAAGCAAGACUGAAUAAAAUCAACAAUAAAUAACAAAAUUGAAUUGGAGUAUCAAAAGCUUCCCUCAGUGAAAUAUAGCAAAGCCCAGAUGGAUGUCCAAUAAAAUUUUAGCAAACAUUAAGGACUUGAUUAUCAUUAUGUAAGCAGUAUUAGAGAAUUUUUAAAAUAUAGAUUACUUCCAAAUUCACCUAGAAAUUCUUUUAUAACCUUUACACCAAAUCAGGAUAGAGACAGUAGAAGAAAAAAUAAAUACAGGUCAAUCUAAUAUAUGAAAAUUUUCUGAGUAAAUGAAAUCCAGGUCUCUUUCGCCAUACAUUUGUAUAUGAGGUUGAACCAUAGGAAAUUACAAUAAUCAACCAUGUUUUACAUAUGUGGCAGAUUUUAUUUUCUGAAGUGGGCUAUGACAGUAGCUUCCAUCUCAUCUCCUCUUCUACAGUGUGAUCUUGCCACUCCUCCCACUUAUAGUCUUGCCCCAUCCUUUGAGUUUUGUUGGCUUGUGAGUCACUUGUAGCCAAAAGAAUGUGGAGGAAGUGAUCAUGUAACUUCGCAGGAUAUAAAAAGCCAUGCGGCUUCUGCCUUGAUUGCAGAGAUCCUUCAUUUGCCAUGUAAGCAGUCCUUGAAGCUGCAGUACUAGGAGGAAAUCUCAAAUAAUCCAUAUAGAGAAACCACAUAGAGAGGCUCUGAGAUUACAUAAAGAGAUGCUUGUUCAGCCCCAUAUGCUCCCGUUCCAUGCCUUUCUGGCUCCAUGAGAAAUUCUGACCCAGAACGGCUCAGUCAGACCUCUCCUGAAUCCCUGACAAACAGGAACCAUCAGAAAUAAUAACGUCUUUGUUGCUAUUUGUGCUAUAAUGUUUUGAGGUGAUACGUUAGACUACAGUAGUGAUUGGAAUAGAAAUUUAGUGUUGGAAGUGGGGUUCUACUUACAUGCAUCACUGGCCUUGGCACUGGAUGAUGAGCAGAAUCUGAAAGGCCCUUGAGUAAAAUAUCAGUAAAACCCAGUGGGCUUUGGGGAUGGUAUUAGCAGAGUCUAAAAGUCAUCAAGGAGGUUGCUGGUGAGAGCUUGAAGGAACACAAGGAAAGCAUUAUUGAAACAUGGAGAAAAUGAGACUUUUUUAUGUAGUGACAGGUGUAUCAACACUGUCACCUAAUGUAAAUGGAAAAUAGAAGAUGUACCUCAUGACCUCAGUGAUAGAGCUAAGUGUUUUCUAGACCCAGUGUUCAGGAUGCUACCUGGCUCCUCAUUGCUUAUAAUAAAAUGAGAGGAAAGAGAACUAAAAAAUGAACCAUUCCAUGGAGGAAAUGGUAAACAGUCUUUUCAGCUUGUAAAGCAUUCUCAAAGUACGAAAGCUCCUCAGGGAAAAGAUGUAAUCCAAGGCUGGCUAUAAUACCCUUAUGUAAGAUUCCAGAAAGAUCUGAAGCGGUGCCUCCUGACCCCCUUCAAUGAAUAAACAAAAAGGACUUCUAAGGACUUGAGAGAAUGCUUCUGUGAGCCCUCUCUCAUAAGCAACAGAACUGCUAAGAAUUUUAAGGGUGAGGUCCCACAAAAGGCCCACUGAGAGCCCAUAGUAGAGAAAGUCUUAUUAAGAGAUUUUUGGGGUGUGGCUUUUGUCUAAUGGAAUGGGUUGUACACAGAUAGCUAAAAAUCCCACACGUUCUUAAAAACAGUGAUGCUAACUUUACAGAUAAGGACAAACUGUAUAAAAAAAGAUAUUUGAACUCUCAACCUUUUUGCUCAGGAAGGAGGUUGAGAAGGAUACUCACUUGCAAACAUGGUCACAUUUUAUGAAAAACCAUGGAUGACUCAGAGAGCAGAACUAAGAUCCAGAGGGUAGAGCAAAGAGCCAUGGAGGAGAAGUCCAAGAAAGCAGAACCAAACCCUAAUCACCGAACUGGUAAUGGGUACCCAGUAGGAUUUAUGGAUUUCUAUGGAACAGUGACUACUCUGUGCCUCCUCUUGUCCCCAUUUUUGAAUAGGAGUAUUGGUAACAGUUUUUCUGUGUCUGCCCCACUGUUACGUUCUGGGUGUGUAAGAUGAAAAUAACUUGUCUCAUAUUUCACAGGCAUUCAGAUUGGGAGAAAUAGCACCUCAGGAACUGCAUCCUCAAGAGUCCCAUCUGCACCUGUAGCAGAGUUUGACGAUGAGAUCCUGGUCUUCAAUCUGAUAUUAUAACGGGAUGAGACAUUGGGAUCUUGGGGGAGGAGAUGGCUGUACUUUGCAUGGGGGGGAUGUGAAUUGUUACAGCCAGAGGGCAGACCGUGGUAAUCCCAAACAUGGCCAAAACAGUAUCUCCUAUCACACAUUCUCUUCCACAGUGUGCCUGCUAUAUAUUUCUCCCAUGAGAGUUGAGGUCGACACCAGCUCCUUGAACCUGGGUGGACUUGUAAUUUGCCUGUAGCCAACAGAAUGCAGCAGAAAUAGGCCAGGUGCAGUGGCUCAUACCUGUAAUCCCAGAGCUUCAGGAGGCCAAGGCAGGAAAAUUGCUUGAGCCCAGGAGUUUGAGACCAGCCUGGGAAACACAGUGAGACCCCGUUUCUAUUUAAGAAAGAAAAAAAAGAAUGCAGCAGAGAUGAAGCUGUGUAACUUCCAAAGCUAGGUCAUAAAAGGUGAUGCAGCUUCCAUCUUGUCACUGGAAUUCACACUCUUGAACCAUUCAGCAGCCAUAUAAGCAGUCCAAUGGCCCUGAGCUGCCCUGCAGUAAGAAAGCCCAAACUAGCUCACACACAGACUACAUCAAGAGUGAGAGAUGCCUAAAACACCCCCAGGCAUUCCAGCCCCUUCUGUUCUAGAUCUAGCCUUAGAAAAAGCUGCCUAGCUGAGCCUAUCUUGAAUUUCUGACCCAGGAAACUAUUAGAUAUAAUAAGUCACUUUUUUUUUUUUUUGAGAUGCACUCUCACUCUUUCCCAGGCUGGAGUGCAGUGGCACGAUCCUGGCUCACUGCAGCCUCCUCCUACUGGGUUCAAGCAGUUCUCUGCCUCAGCCUCCCAAGUAGCUGGGAUUACAGGUGCUCGCCACCAUACUUGGCUAAUUUUUGUAUUUUUAGUAGAGAUGGGGUUUCACCAUCUUGGGCAGGCUGGUCUUGAACUCCUGACCUCAUGAUCCACCUGCCUCGGCCUCCCAAAGUGCUGGGAUUACAGGCGUAAGCCACUGCGCCUGGCCAAUAAGUCUCUUUUUUUAGGUAAUCAAGUUAAAAUAAUAAGUCACUAAAUUUUGAGGUGUUCUGUUAUGUAGAAGAGUGACUGGACCAACCCAUAAAAAGGACAACUUCAUAUAGUUCAACUUUUUUUUUUUUUUUUUUUUUUUUUGAUACAGAGUCUCGUUCUGUCACCCAGGCUGGAGUGCAGUGGCAUAAUUUCAGCUCAUGGCAACCUCCGCCUCCAAGGUUCAAGUGAUUAUCAUGCCUCAGCCUCCCAAGUAGCUGAGAUUACGGGCACCUGCCACCACGCCUGGAUAAUGUUUGUAUUUUUAGUAGAGGUGGGGUUUCACCAUGUUGACUAGGCUGGUCUCGAACUCCUGACCUCAGGUGAUCUGCCCGCCUUGGCCUCCCAAAGUGCUGGGAUUACAGGCAUGAGCCAUUGCAUCUGGCCUAGUUCAACUUUAUAAAUAAAUAUGUCAAAGAUAAUUCAAUAUUAAAGUUUAUAUAUUUAUCAUUUUAACCAAAUAAUGUAGAAAUAGAGUGAUAUGAAACAUAAAUACCUAUAUAGGUUAAGAAAAAUAUUCAAUAAAUUGGAACAAUUCUUUGUUAUAAAAUUCUUAAGAAACUCAGAAUAAAAUGCAACACCUUUUUACGAUUAUAAACCCCUCAGCAAACAUACUUCAAGCAGAACCUUACGAACAGUAUAAUUAAAAUGAGGAACCGCUGA